AGUUUGUUUUAUUUGAAGCAACUUUUGUGUGCUUUUCUAGAAGUCCGAAGGCUUCGUUGCAGAUACUAUUUGGCUAUGCUAGGAUGGGUUCGAUCAUUUUUAGAGUUGGGGAAUACAAUUAAACCAUGCCGGGCUACACCUGGCCUUCUCACCACUCCAGUACCUGCCACUGAGACAUCGUAAACAUGUUCAGAGGAGAGUGUUCAGCUUUUAUGGGAUGAAUAUUUGGUGUGUUUUCAUGCUUUAAUGCAUGACUCCUUCUCCAAGUUGUCUUUCUGGAAAGCUGUGGAGACUCUUAAGGGCUUUUCCUGAGAUAAUUACUGAACGGCUUUAGCCCGGCCAGCCCCCUGGGGCGGUGGGAACAGGUGUAAUCCUCAUUAAGUUUUUUCGUGGUGAAGAAUGGAGAUGUCAAAAUAAGUAAAAAGUGGAAAUGUUUAGGUCUUUGUCCACAUGUUUGAAUUAACAAAGCUUAUCUGAAUUUUUAAAAAAUCAAACUCAAACCACUUUUGGUCAGCUAGCCUUAAAAUUGUUUGAAAAAUCAUGUGAAUAAAUUUACCUAAUUAGAAAUUUUUUAGCAUUUCAGUGGAUUCGUGUUAAUUGUGUUGUAGGAUAUUACAGAAUGUUUAGAGAACUGAGUCACAAUGAGGUUAUUCUGAGUAGUGCUCUCACUAGCAUAAGGUGAGAGUUAAUGUAAAAUUUAAAAACUGAAUGAAUCACAUUUUAAUAAGGGAACGGGUGAAAAGCAAUUGGUUCAUUUUUCAUUAUUAUAUUUUUCAUUACUUAUAUGUUUUAAAUAUAUAUUUUCAAUAAUUUCACAAAGUUAUUUAUUCAUUUACUCAAACUCCUACAUAUACCAGCCACUGUGCUGGCUUCUGGAGAUCUGAAUAAUAAUAGUUACUCCUUAUAGAAUGCUUAUUUUAUACCAGUAGAUAUUUUACAUAGAUUACCUUUUUACCUUUUUCAUCUAUAAGUAUUUAUUGAGUACCUACAAUGUAUUGUGCUGGGUGUUGGGGCGAUAGUGGUGCACAAGACAGUCGUGAUUCCUGCCCUUAUCUAGGUGGGGAAUCUAGGCAGGAAAUAAAAUAUAUUGCUAAACUAAUAGCAGCUUUUGAAAGGUAAAUCAUAUCACAUCAUUCUUCUGUUCAAAACCCUCCAUUGGCUUCCUAUGUCUCUCUGAGUGAAUGGCAAAGACCUGACAGUGGCUCCCAGAACAACCUCUUUUGGCUUCCCUGCCUCUCCAUGCUGUGACUUUCCUAUCUUAUCUGUUGCUCUCCUCCCUACUCGAGUGUCUACAGCCAAACCAGCUUUCUUGCUGCAUGAGGGCCUUUGGACUUGUUGUGCGCUGCCUGGAAUGACCCCCUGUCCCUAGCUCCCAUAUCUCUAAUGGCUCUUGUUGAUCUGACCCCCUUCACUUCUUUACUUGAUGUUAUUUUGUCAGUGAGCCUUCACUAACCUCCAAAUUUAAAAUCACAGCCAUCCUCGCGACUCCCAUUCCUCCUUUCAUAAGUUGUUAUUUUUCCUCCGUAGCACUUAUGGCUAUAUCAUAUGUUGCUUGUUUAUUGUCUGUCUUUUUCGGGAGAUUUUAUAUCCUUCAGAACUGUAUCACAGCUGUUUUAUUCACUGUUACACCUUCAGAAUCUGGAACGGUAACUGGCGUAUAGCAGGUCCUCAAUAACUUGAAUGAGUGUUGAGUGGAAAGAAGGGUAUAACAGAGUGCUGGGACAUGGAAUAACCAAGGCCUCCUAGAAUACUGGUGAGAAGGCCUCUAGGUGGAAGUGACAUUUAACUGAGACUUGAAGAUGAGAAGGAGCUAGCCAUGUUGUUGUGGCAUAAGAGGUUGUAGAGAGGAGACAGGCAUGGAAGAAGAUCCGGCCGAGAGAUAGGAUGCUCAAAGGCCUCCAGGCAGGAAAGAGCUAGGUGGUGUGUGGAUUUAUUGGAACUGAGAGGUCAUUGUGGCUGAGCACUGUCAAGUUAAGGGAGGGUAGGACUAAAUGACAGGGUGGAAAUCAGGUGUCAGAUCAUGCAGGGCCUUUCUGGAGAAAUUAACAUGGAAUCCUCAUAUGUAGCCUAUUAGCCCUUUUUAUGGUUUAAGAAACUGGGCAUCAGGGAGAUUGAAUAACUUUCUGAGAUUAUGCAGUAGGUGAGUGGCAGCGCCUAGAAUACAAAGCCAGGCUCGCAGACUCUAACGAACCUGUAUCUGACCACUAUGUCAAAAUCAAAAGACAGUCCCUGUCCUGGUGAAGCUGUUAGUCUAGUGGGAAGACAAGCUAUUGCAGUAUACACAUGUGCUCCUGGGGGCUGUGGGAGGAGGGAAGCCCCUAGUUCUGCCUGGGAGUGGGACAGGCCAAAUUGGAAACAUACAAUCAUUUUUCCUUUUUUAUUAUUGUGAAAUAUUUCAGAUUGGCAACAUCUUAAUUAAGAAAUAAUAUUAAAUACAAUAGCCUAUUCUCUGAGUCUUCACUGUAUGUUCCCCUCCUUUUUUUCUUUUUAAAGACAAAAUGCUUGCUUUCACAUGUACAAAGGAUCUGUGUCAUAAUGCCCCCUUUCCUACUUUCAUCAAAUAAAAGAUUAUGUCUGGAGUAGUGUAAAUUCACUUAUUUUAUUUUUUUGAGACAAGGUCUCGUUCUAUCACCCAGGCUGGAGUACAGUGGUGCGAUCAUGGCUCACUGUAGCCUCUACCUCCUGGGCCCAAGUGAUUCUCCCACCCCGGCCUCCCAAGUAACUGACUACAGGUGCACACUACCAUGCCUGGCCAACUGUGAAUUUUUUUGUAGAGAAGAGGUCUCACCAUGUUGCCUAGGCUGGUCUCCAACUCCUGGCCUCAAGUGAUCCUCCCACCUCAGCCUCCCAAAGUGCUGGAUUACAGGCAUGAGUCUGCCCUUGGCCUCGUGUUUACAUUUGAGAAGUUUUUGACUUAUGUAUAGACCUGUGGAACUGUCUCCCUGUAGCUCCUUGCUAUACCCUGAAUCCCUCUUCCUCAUCCAGCCAAUGAUAGCUUUCUGUCUCUGUGGAUUAGUUUGCGUUUUUUAGAAUGUUAUGUAAAUGGAAUCAUGUAGUAAGUUCUCUUCUUUGCCUGGCUUUUGCUUAGCAUAAUUAUUUUGAGACUCAUCCACAUUGUAUCAAUAGCUGAUUUCUUUUUAUUGUUAAGUAAUACUCCAUUGUACUGAUAGACGCCAGUUCAUGUAUCUUUUCACCCAUUGAUAGACAUUUAGGUUGUUUCUGGUUUUGGGCUAUUAAAAAUAAAGCUGCCAUGAACAUUAUACACAGUCUUUGUAUGCAUAUCUUUCAUUUCCCCUGGGUAGAUGUCUAGGAGUAGAAUGACUAGAUCCUAUGGUAGGCAUAUGUUUAAUUUUUCAAAGAACUACUAUACUUUUCCAAAGUGGUUAUAUAAUAUAACCAAAAUAGUCUAUGAGGGUUCCAGUUGCCCCAGAUCCUUGCCAACAGUUGGGGUGGUUAGGCUUUUAUAGCCAUUCUGUUGGGUGUGUAGUGACACCUCAUUGUGGUUUUAAUUUCCAUUUCCCUGAUGACUAAUGAUGUUGAGCAUCAUUUCAUAUGCUUAUUUACCAUCCAUUUAUCUUCUUUGUUGAAGUGUCUACUCAAAUUUUUUGCCCGUUUUCUUGCAUUGUUUUCCUUCUUAUUGAGUUUUGAGAGUUCUUUGUGUAUUCUGGAUGCAAGUCAUUUGUCACGUGUAAGAUUUGCAAAUAUUUCCAUUCAGUCUUAUCUUAGUCCAUUUUGUGCUGCCAUUACAGAAUACCAUAGAUUGGGUAAUUUAUAAUGAACAGAAAUUUAUUGGCUCAUGGUUCUAGAAUCUGGGAAGUCUAAGAUUGAUGGGGCGACAUCUGGUGAGAGCAUUUUUGCUGUAUCAUUACAUGACAGAAGGGCAAAGAGAGGGUGAGAAAGAAGCAAAAUGGAGCUGUUUUAUUAUUUUUAUUUUAUUAUUUAUUUAUUUAUUUAAGACACAGUCUCACUCUGUCACCCAGGCUGGAGUGCAGUGACACAGUCUCAGCUCACUGCAACCUCUGCCUCCUGGGUUCUAGUGAUUGUGGUACCUGGGAUUACAGGUGUGCGUCUCCACACCGGCCUUUUUUUUUUUUUUUUUUUUUUUUUUUUUUUUGAUUUUUAGUAGAGACAGGGUUUCACUGUGUUGGCCAGGAUGGUCUUGAACUCCUGGCCUCAAGUGAUCUGCCCACCUUGGCCUCCCAAAGUGCUGGGAUUACAGGCAUGAGCCACUGCACCCAGCCUAUUUUUUUUUUUGAGACAGUAUCUCGCUGUGUUGCCCAGGCUGGAGUGCAGUGGCUUGAUCUCAGCUCACUGCAACCUCUGCCUCCCAGGUUCAAGCGAUUCUCCUGCCUUAGCCUCCUGAGUAGCUGGGACUCCAGGUGCGUGCCACCACUCUCAGCCUGAUUUAUUCCUUUAUAAGGAACCCACUCCUGCGAUGAUGGCAUUAAUCCAUUAAUGACAGCAGAGCCCUUAUAACCUAUCACCUGAUAAAAGUUCCAUCUCUUAAUACUGUAAUAUUGUAACAGUAUUGCCUCUUAAUAAUGUUACGAUGGCGAUUAAAUUUCACCAGAGUUUUGGAGGGGACAUUUAAACCAUAGCAAAUUUAUUACAUUCUCUUAACAAUAUCUUUUGAAGAUACUGUUCUUAAUUUUGAUGAAGUACAAUUUGUCAAUUUAUUCUUUAUGGAUUGUACUUUUGGUAUUAUUAUCUAAGAAAUCUGCCUAAUUCAAAGUCAAAAAGGCUUUCUCCUAUGAUUUUUUUCUAAAAUUUUUAUAGGUUUUGGUUUAACAUUUAGGUUCAUGUACUUUAAUUUUUGUUUAUGGUGUGAAUAUGGGUGGAAGUUUACCCCACCUAUGCCAGGAACAUUUGGUAAUUUUUGGAGACAGUGUCUGGAAACCAUGUCUGGUGUAGGGACGAGGGGCAUUUGUUCCCAGCCAUCUACUGGGCAGAAGUCUAGGAUGCUGCUAGAUACCCUACAGUGGAUAGGUGAGAUCCUCUCAAUAGAGAAUUAUUCAGCCAAAGUGUUAGUAGUGCCAGGGUUGAGACACUCUAGGCUUGAGGUUUAUUAAUUUUAUUGAACUCCAUGAACCAGCUGUUGGUUUCAUUGAUAUUGUUUAAUAUUUUUCUAUUUUCCCUUUGAUUGAUUUUCACUCAGAUCUUUAUUUUUCCCUUCUACUUUUGGGUUUAAUUUGUUCUUAUUCCAGUUUCCUUAGGUCAUUGAUUUGUGACUUUUCUUCUUUUCUGAUAUAGGUGUUUAGUCUUUUAAAUUUAUUCCUCAGUACUACUUUAGUGACAUCUCACAAAUUUUGAUAUGGUGUGAUUUUAUUUGUAUUUAGUUAAAAAUACUUUUAAAAUUGGCUGGGCGUGGUGGCUCACACCUGUAAUCCCAGCAGUUUGGGAGGCCAAGGCAGGCGGAUCACGAGGUCAAGAGCUGGAGACCAGCCUGGCCAACAUAGUGAAAUCCCAUCUCUACUAAAAAUACAAAAUUAGCUGGGUGUGGUGGCACAUGCCUGUAAUUCCAGCUACUUGGGAGGCUGAGGCAGGAGAAUUGCUUGAACUCAGGGGGUGGAGGUUACAGUGAGCUGAGAUCAUGACGCUGCAGUCCAGCCUGGGCAACAGAGCAAGACUCUGCCUCGGGAAAAAGAGAAAACAAAGAAAGAAGCAAGUCACUAUGUGCAGCCUGCACUAAAGGAGUGGACUCCACUCCUUUCCUCCCUCCUUUCUCUCUUUUCUUUCUCUCUCUCUUUCUCCCUUCUCCCCUUCCUUCCCUCCCUCCCUCCCUCCCUCCCUCCCUUCCUCCCUUCCUUCCUUCGUUCCUACCAUCUGUCUGUCUGUCUAGCUUUGUUGCCCAGCUGGCUGGAGUGCAGUGGCACCAUCUUGGCUCACUGCAACCUCUGCCUCUCUGGCCCAAGUGAUCUGCCUGCUUUGGCCUCCCAAAGUACUAGGAUUAUAGGUGUGAGCCUCUGUGCCUGGCCUAGAAACUAAUUUUCUUAAACUAAAUCCACUAAAUUAUCAUAGAGCAGACCAUUGCUGUUAUAGAAACAUAUUUUAGAAUACUGCAGAGUAUUACAAUAUUCAGAGCACCUGCACUUGGAGAACCCUCCCCUCCAGACAGGUUCUGCAGGGUGCACUGCCUCCUUUUCUUUCCUCUGGGCUGCAUUAGGAGGAGGGAGGUGAAUGGGGAGAAGGAAUCAAUCUUCCUGUGUUGACAUUUUCCAGACCCUGAGAAACGUUGAGUUGAAAGAUAAGUGUGAAAGCAUCUCUUUCUUUUGAUGGUGUGUGAGAUGAAAAGCACUUGCUAAUAGCCCCUCAGGUCAAAGUAACACAUUUGACAAAAAGGAGCCUCAAGCUUUUGCUUGUCAGUGUCCAUAUUUGAUUGGAAAUUUCAAUCUGAGAUUUGGUGCUUGGAUUUUCCUAGAAUUUGCCAAUUACUUGUUGCUCUGGUUCCAGCUGACUUUUAGUCUUCCUUUGGGUACUACCACUGGGUGCAGUUUGUUAUCAGUGAGUAGCUCUUCUCUAUCGGGCUGUGUAAAUGUACCCCUAUUUAAUUCAUUCAACAAAUUAUUUUUUAAAUACUUAUUGAAUCUGGGCUCUGACACACAGGUAAAAGUCAAUGUCUCUUGCCACUUGUAAGCUGUCUAGAAGCAGAAAGGCCCAUAAGCAGAGGAACAUGCAAUCAGUGGGGUAAUUGGUAGUCACUGCAGUGGAAACAUGAGCAGGGCAAAGCAUGGUCAGCUGGAGCAGUGGUUCUCAAAGUAGGGUCCAGGGACCAGGAGCAGCCAACCUAUUGAGUAUAACCUUGACAGUGGGGCCCAGCAAUCUGUGUUUAAUAAGCCUUCUAAGUGAUUCUGAUGCAUGCUCCAGACUGUGAACCAUGGGCAUAGAGGAUUAGACAAUCUUUGAGAUUUUUUCCAGCUCUUCAAGUCUAUGCAUAUGGUUAAGAAAUGUGAUAUUUACCACAUUGUUUUUUUUUUUUUUUUUUGAGACGGAGUCUUACUCUGUUGCCCAGGCUGGAGUGCGGCGGCACAAUCUCAGCUCACUGCAACCUUCGCCUCCUGGGUUCAAGCGAUUAUCCUACCUCAGACUCCUGAGUAGCUGGGAUUACAGGUGCGCACCACCACGCCCAGCUAAUUUUUGUAUUUUUAGUAGAGACGGGGUUUCACCAUGUUGGUCAUGCUGGUCUCGAACUCCUGACCUCGUGAUCCGCCCACCUCAGCCUCCCAAAGUGCUGGGAUUACAGGCAUGAGCCACCGUGCCUGGCCCUACCCCGUUGUAUUUUAAGAGCAUUAGUUGGCACUAAUAUCAUAUAAAACAUUAAUUGCAGUGUAGGCUGGGCACUGUAGCAUAUGCCUGUAAUCCCAGCAUUUUGGGAGGCUGAGGCGAGAGGAUCACAUGAGCCCAGGAGUUUGAGACCAGCCUGGGCAACAUAGUGAGACCCCAAUCUCAAAAAAAAAAAUUAGCUGGGCUAUGGUGGUGCAUGUCUAUAGUCCCAGGUACUAGGGAGGCUGAGGUGGGAGGAUCGCCUGAGCCUGGGGGAUUGAGGCUGCAGUGAGCCGUGAGAGACACAGUGAGACCCCGACUAAAAAGAAAAAAAGGAAUGUAGGUAAAACAAAUUCAAUUUUACUAUGUGUGUUGUUGAAGUGAGCACAUAAAACAAAUUCAAAAUGAUACAGUUAUGUUUGACAGUGGAGCAAUAGUAAAUUGGACUUAAAAAACUUUAUUAUGAAAAAUUUCAAAUAUAUUCAAAAGCAGAGAUAAUAGUAAAAUGUACUAUUGCAUAACGAUUACCCAGAAUGAAUAUUAUUAAAUCCUGUCAAUCUGGUUUUACCCAGGUCCUCACAUAUCCCACCCGUGCUGGAUUAUUUUGAAGCAAAUUUUAUACAUCAUAUCAUUUUAUCCUUAAAUAAUUGGAUUUUAAAUUAUUUGAGAUAUUAAAGUGCUAGAAAUGAAUUUGAAACCAAAUCAUGUGUAGCCAUUUCCUGGUUUCCCUUACAUUAUAGAUAAAACUUAUCUAGAGCUAAUUUACACAAAAGUUGGAUAAAACAAAACAACAGUUGGACACAUGUACAUAUAUUCGUAUUUGCAUAACAUCUACUAAAAGUAUACUUUUUUUGUUGUUGAGGCGAAGUCUCGCUCUGUCACCCAGGUGGGAGUGCAGCGUGGUGUGAUUAUGGCUUAUUGCAGCCCUGACCUCCUUGGCUCAAGUGAUCCUCCAGCCUCGUGUUUUGAUAUUUUGUAGAGACCGAGAUCUCACUGUGUUGCCCAGGCUGGUCUCAAACUUCUGGGCUCAAGAAAUCCUCCUGCUUUAGCCUCCUAAGGGGCUGGGAUUAGAGGCGUGAACCACUGUGCCUGGCAAAAAUAAGUAUACUUGUCACUACCGUGAAUACAUUUUAUUAAAACAUUUUAUUUACUGUCAUUAUGUUAGCAAUAUGUGCAUUAUACUUAUAGAUAAUAUUCUAGAAUAGUAAGAAAGACUAUACACGCAUGCCCUGCCAAAAUUGAAUUGUUGCACUUGAAGGGGAAAUUUUAAUUUGAAAGGCAGGUUUUUAGGAAGGUAGAUAUUAGGUUUUGGGGCAGUUUUUAUUAGAAGGUUUUGGGGCAGUUUUGUUUUUUUUUUGUUUUGUUUUGUUUUUUUGGAGACAGAGUCUCACUCUGUUGCCAGGCUGGAGUGCAGUGGCGUGAUCUUGGCUCACUGCAGCCUCUGCCUCCUGGGUUCAAGUGAUUCUACUGCCUCAGCCUCCUGAGUAGCUGGAGCUAUAGGCAUGCACCACCACACCUGGCUAAUUUUUGUAUUUUUAGUAGAGGUGGAAUUUCACCAUGUUGGCCAGGCUGAUCUCAAACUCUUGGCCUCAAGUGACCUGCCCGCCUCAGCCUCCGAAAAUGCUGGGAUUAUGGGCCUGAGCCACCGUGCCUGGCCUUGGGGCAGAUUUUUAAUAUAUGUAAAUUAAGAAUUCUCAGUACUCAUUUCAGCAGUUAUGUUGCCUCAUUUGGAAAGAAAAGGUAUUCAGCAUGUGGGGAUGCAUAAUACAUUUUAAAAAUCCGUUCGUCUUAGUCAAUGUGCUCCAUGGUGUCUUUUUUUCAAGGUUCGAGAUGACACAUUUAGUAGGAGAUCAGGUUAUGGGAUAGUUCAUGUUUGGAGAGGGGACAGAAUUGAUUUACAGACAUACCACCUGUUUUCUCCUACUUUGGCUUUGGAGGACAAGUUGUAGUAUCCUGAGGAAAAGCUGAUUGUAUCACUUAUGACUGAGAUUUUCAUCUUUAGCCGCUUCUGUGUGAUACAUGAAUUAAUGGGUCAUAACAUAGGAGUUAGCUAAUUUUCAUUUUAAAAUAUUACUCAGAAGAUAUUUUUAUCUUAAUUGUACAUUUCAACAACAUAAAUAAGCUGUUCAAGACUGUCUCCCAUGCCUCCAAAACAAAUAAAAACCCCCCACAACUCAAAUGCAUAUAAGCUGUUACUAUAGUAUAAUGGUGAGUUAUAGCCAGUGUAUGAUGGGAUUGUUGAUAGAAUAAUGCAUAUUAGAGCUUUUAGUUCAAAAAUUUGAGAUAGUGAUUCAGAAAGAAAAAAAGGAAUGAUUAUCAUGAAUUCUGUUUAUUAGAAUUCUGUUUAUUAAAGAGUUAAAGAUAUGUUUUAUUUUUUUAUCUUUAUUAUCAUUAUUUUUUCGAGAUGGAGUUUCGCCCUUGUUGCCAGCGCUGGAGUGCAGUGGUGUGAUCUUGGCUCACUGCAACCUCCACCUCCCGGGUUCAAGCAAUUCUGCCUCAGCCUCCUGAAUAGCUGGGAUUACAGGCGCACGGCACCACGCUUGACUAAUUUUUUGUAUUUUUCGUAGAAACGGGGUUAGCCAGGCUGGUCUCGAACUCCUGACCUCAGGUGAUCCACCCGCCUCAGCCUCCCAAAGUGCUGGGAUUACAGGUGUGAGCCACGGCGCCUGGCCAAGAUGUGUUUUAUUAUUUGCACUUGUGUAAUGGCAAAGAAAAUAGGUUACUAAGCUUGCUCUUGUUAGAAUAUCCUUUGUAGUCACUCAUUUGAUGAUGUUGAGUAAGAAUCUUUCCUCUGUUAAUACGUCUUUGUUUAAAAGAAAAUAAGUUACCUUUGUAGUCUUUGUACAUUUUUCUUUGCAGAAAGUUUCCCCUCUGCUGGAUAAUAAUUAAUUUUAUAAAAGUGUUUAAUCCAGUACUGAUUAUAUUCCCUUGUGAGCUGGAUGAAAAGAAACUUCUGAAUGUUUGUAACCACAGAUUGAUGAUUUGGUUACAAAGACUCUCUGUUGGUGAUGGUUUCUGAGAACUGGAAGUUCACUUCUUCAACUGAGAUGGACAUGAUAUAAUCUCCAUUGAGUCAAAGAAUGGCAUCUAGUCCUGAGCUUCCCACCGAAGAUGAACAGGGUUCCUGGGGCAUCGACGAUCUCCAUAUUUCAUUGCAAGCUGAACAGGAAGACACCCAGAAGAAAGCCUUCACGUGCUGGAUAAACUCACAGUUGGCCAGGCACACUUCUCCCUCAGUUAUAUCCGACCUAUUCACAGACAUUAAAAAGGGGCAUGUCCUCCUGGAUCUGCUAGAAGUACUUUCUGGGCAACAGUUGCCUCGGGAUAAAGGAUCUAAUACCUUCCAGUGUAGAAUCAAUAUAGAACAUGCCUUGACAUUCCUAAGAAACCGAUCAAUUAAGCUAAUAAAUAUUCAUGUUACUGAUAUCAUUGAUGGAAACCCAUCCAUUAUCCUUGGCCUAAUUUGGACAAUUAUCCUGCACUUUCAUAUUGAGAAGCUUGCCCAGACUCUUUCUUGCAAUUACAAUCAGCCUUCCCUGGAUGAUGUGAGUGUGGUUGACUCAUCUCCUGCCUCAAGUCCUCCAGCUAAGAAAUGCUCUAAAGUGCAAGCAAGAUGGCAAAUGUCUGCAAGAAAGGCCCUUCUUUUGUGGGCUCAGGAACAAUGCGCCACCUAUGAGUCUGUCAAUGUGACCGAUUUUAAGUCAAGUUGGAGAAAUGGGAUGGCUUUUUUGGCCAUCAUUCAUGCCUUGCGACCAGACCUAAUUGACAUGAAGAGUGUGAAGCAUAGAUCCAACAAAGACAAUCUGAGAGAGGCCUUCAGAAUUGCAGAACAAGAAUUAAAAAUCCCCAGAUUGCUGGAACCAGAAGAUGUGGAUGUUGUUGAUCCUGAUGAAAAGUCCAUCAUGACCUAUGUGGCACAGUUUCUGCAGUAUUCCAAAGAUGCCCCUGGGACUGGAGAGGAGGCUCAGGGAAAGGUGAAAGAUGCUAUGGGCUGGUUAACUCUGCAAAAGGAAAAACUACAGAAGUUGCUAAAGGAUUCAGAGAAUGAUACCUACUUUAAAAAGUAUAAUAGCCUGCUGUCCUUUAUGGAGUCAUUCAAUGAAGAAAAAAAGUCCUUUUUGGAUGUCCUGUCAAUAAAACGGGAUCUGGAUGAGCUGGACAAGGAUCAUUUACAGUUGAGAGAAGCCUGGGAUGGCCUCGAUCACCAGAUUAAUGCAUGGAAAAUAAAGCUAAAUUAUGCCUUGCCCCCACCCCUCCAUCAAACUGAAGCUUGGCUCCAGGAGGUAGAAGAGCUUAUGGAUGAAGAUUUGUCAGCCUCCCAGGAUCACUCUCAAGCCGUGACUCUGAUACAAGAGAAAAUGACUUUAUUCAAGAGCCUGAUGGAUAGAUUUGAGCAUCAUUCGAACAUUCUCCUUACCUUUGAAAAUAAGGAUGAAAAUCACUUGCCAUUGGUACCACCUAACAAAUUGGAGGAAAUGAAAAGACGAAUCAACAACAUUUUGGAGAAAAAAUUUAUUCUACUUCUAGAAUUUCAUUACUACAAGUGCUUAGUUCUUGGUUUGGUAGAUGAAGUGAAAUCAAAAUUGGAUAUUUGGAACAUUAAAUAUGGGAGCAGAGAAUCUGUGGAAUUAUUGCUGGAAGACUGGCAUAAAUUUAUUGAAGAAAAAGAAUUCCUAGCUCGACUUGAUACUUCUUUUCAAAAAUGUGGAGAAAUUUAUAAGAAUUUGGCUGGAGAAUGUCAGAAUAUUAAUAAACAGUAUAUGAUGGUGAAAUCUGAUGUUUGUAUGUAUAGAAAAAAUAUAUAUAAUGUGAAGUCCACUCUACAAAAAGUGCUGGCAUGUUGGGCUACUUAUGUGGAAAACCUUCGCUUACUAAGGGCUUGCUUUGAGGAGACAAAGAAGGAAGAAAUUAAAGAGGUACCCUUUGAGACACUAGCCCAGUGGAAUCUAGAACACGCUACUUUAAAUGAAGCAGGAAAUUUCUUAGUCGAAGUCAGCAAUGAUGUGGUUGGAUCAUCUAUUUCUAAAGAACUGAGAAGGCUGAAUAAAAGAUGGAGAAAGUUGGUUUCAAAAACUCAACUUGAAAUGAACCUGCCACUGAUGAUAAAAAAACAGGAUCAGCCCACUUUUGACAAUUCUGGAAAUAUUCUAUCUAAAGAAGAGAAAGCAACUGUUGAGUUUUCAACAGAUAUGUCAGUAGAACUUCCUGAAAAUUAUAAUCAAAAUAUAAAGGCUGGAGAGAAACAUGAAAAAGAAAAUGAAGAAUUCACAGGGCAACUAAAAGUGGCUAAAGAUGUUGAAAAACUCAUUGGACAAGUGGAAAUCUGGGAGGCAGAAGCCAAAUCUGUUUUGGAUCAAGAUGAUGUGGACACCUCAAUGGAAGAAUCUUUGAAGCAUCUUAUUGCCAAAGGCUCUAUGUUUGAUGAGCUUAUGGCAAGAAGUGAAGAUAUGUUACAAAUGGAUAUACAAAAUAUUUCAAGCCAGGAGUCCUUUCAACAUGUUCUCACAACUGGGCUUCAGGCAAAGAUUCAAGAAGCUAAAGAGAAAGUCCAGAUCAAUGUGGUAAAACUCAUUGCAGCGUUGAAGAACUUAACUGACGUUUCACCAGAUUUGGACAUCAGGCUGAAGAUGGAAGAAUCCCAGAAGGAACUUGAAUCAUAUAUGAUGAGGGCUCAGCAGUUACUGGGGCAAAGAGAGAGCCCCGGUGAACUCAUUUCAAAACACAAGGAAGCACUAAUAAUUUCUAAUACAAAAAGUCUGGCCAAGUAUUUGAAAGCUGUUGAAGAACUAAAAAAUAAUGUAACUGAGGACAUAAAGAUGUCUUUAGAAGAAAAGAGUAGAGAUGUCUGUGCCAAAUGGGAGUCUCUUCAUCAUGAACUGUCUUUAUAUGUUCAACAACUAAAAAUAGAUAUUGAAAAAGGAAAGCUUAGUGACAAUAUUUUAAAACUUGAAAAGCAAAUAAAUAAAGAAAAGAAACUUAUCCGUAGAGGAAGGACCAAGGGUCUCAUCAAAGAACAUGAGGCCUGCUUUUCUGAGGAAGGCUGCCUGUACCAGCUUAAUCACCACAUGGAAGUCCUGAGGGAGCUGUGUGAAGAGCUGCCUUCACAGAAGAGUCAACAAGAAGUGAAGAGACUACUCAAAGAUUAUGAACAAAAGAUAGAAAGACUUCUGAAAUGUGCUUCCGAGAUUCAUAUGACACUGCAGCCCACAGCGGGAGGCACGUCGAAAAACGAGGGGACCAUCACCACAUCUGAGAAUAGAGGAGGGGAUCCCCACAGUGAGGCACCAUUUGCAAAAUCAGAUAAUCAGCCAUCAACUGAAAAGGCAAUGGAACCCACUAUGAAGUUUAGCCUGGCAUCAGUGUUAAGGCCUCUGCAAGAAGAAAGCAUUAUGGAAAAGGAUUACAGUGCAUCUAUAAAUAGUUUACUAGAGAGGUAUGAUACAUACAGAGAUAUUCUUGAACACCACCUGCAAAACAACAAAUUCAGGAUUACUUCUGAUUUCUCUAGUGAAGAGGACAGGAGUAGUUCUUGUCUGCAGGCUAAACUGACAGAUCUACAGGUCAUAAAAAAUGAAACUGAUGCUCGCUGGAAAGAGUUUGAAAUUAUUUCAUUGAAGUUAGAAAAUCAUGUGAAUGACAUAAAAAAGCCUUUUGUAAUUAAGGAAAGAGACACACUAAAGGAAAGAGAAAGAGAGCUUCAGAUGACUCUUAAUACCAGAAUGGAAUCUUUAGAGACAGCACUGCGGCUUGUGUUACCUGUAGAGAAGGCAUCACUUCUUCUCUGUGGCUCGGACCUGCCUCUCCAUAAAAUGGCCAUCCAGGGAUUUCAUCUCAUUGAUGCUGAUCGCAUCUAUCAACACCUAAGGAAUAUCCAAGAUUCCAUAGCAAAACAGAUUGAAAUAUGUAACCGCUUAGAAGAGCCAGGCAACUUUGUAUUAAAGGAGUUACACCCAUUUGAUCUACACGCAAUGCAGAAUAUUAUACUGAAAUACAAAACACAAUUUGAAGGAAUGAACCACAGGGUGCAGAGGAGUGAAGAUACUCUCAAAGCUCUGGAAGACUUUUUGGCGUCUCUCAGAACAGCUAAACUCUCUGCUGAGCCCGUUACAGACCUUUCAGCCUCAGAUACACAGGUGGCACAAGAAAAUACGUUGACAGUAAAAAAUAAAGAGGGAGAAAUUCAUCUGAUGAAAGACAAGGCCAAACAUUUGGAUAAAUGUUUGAAGAUGCUCGAUAUGAGCUUUAAAGAUGCUGAACGGGGUGAUGACACCUCCUGUGAAAACCUGCUUGAUGCUUUUUCAAUAAAGUUAUCUGAGACACAUGGCUAUGGGGUACAGGAGGAAUUCACUGAGGAAAACAAAUUACUAGAGGCUUGUAUUUUCAAAAAUAAUGAACUCCUUAAAAAUAUUCAAGAUGUGCAGAGUCAAAUCAGUAAAAUUGGUCUUAAGGAUCCUACUGUUCCAGCUGUGAAACAUCGGAAAAAAUCAUUAAUCAGACUGGAUAAGGUUCUAGAUGAAUAUGAAGAAGAGAAGAGACAUUUACAAGAAAUGGCUAAUUCUCUUCCACACUUCAAAGAUGGCAGAGAAAAAACCGUGAAUCAACAGUGCCAAAAUACAGUAGUCUUGUGGGAGAAUACCAAAGCCUUGGUCACCGAAUGUCUUGAACAAUGUGGGAGAGUUUUGGAGCUCUUAAAACAAUAUCAGAAUUUUAAAAGCAUCUUGACAACUUUGAUUCAAAAAGAAGAGAGUGUCAUCUCCCUGCAGGCUUCGUACAUGGGAAAGGAGAACCUGAAGAAAAGGAUAGCAGAGAUUGAAAUUGUCAAAGAAGAAUUUAAUGAGCAUUUAGAAGUUGUAGACAAGAUAAACCAGGUCUGCAAAAAUCUACAAUUUUAUCUAAAUAAAAUGAAAACUUUUGAAGAGCCCCCUUUUGAAAAAGAGGCUAAUAUUAUUGUGGAUAGAUGGCUUGAUAUAAAUGAGAAGACAGAAGAUUACUAUGAAAAUCUUGGUCGAGCUCUAGCUUUGUGGGACAAACUUUUUAACUUAAAAAAUGUCAUUGAUGAGUGGACAGAAAAGGCCCUUCAAAAAAUGGAAUUACAUCAAUUGACUGAAGAGGACAGAGAAAGGCUGAAGGAAGAAUUACAAGUCCAUGAACAAAAAACUUCAGAAUUUUCUAGAAGAGUGGCUGAAAUACAGUUUUUGCUCCAAAGCAGUGAAAUACCUCUUGAAUUGCAGGUCAUGGAGUCCUCUAUUUUGAACAAGAUGGAACAUGUACAGAAGUGCUUAACAGGAGAAUCCAACUGCCAUGCACUCAGUGGCAGCACUGCUGAGCUAAGGGAGGAUCUCGACCAAGCCAAGACCCAGAUCGGGAUGACUGAAUCCCUCUUAAAAGCCCUGUCUCCUUCUGACAGCUUGGAGAUCUUCACUAAACUAGAGGAGAUACAACAGCAGAUUCUACAGCAAAAACACAGUAUGAUAUUACUUGAGAAUCAAAUAGGUUGUCUGACUCCUGAACUCUCUGAAUUGAAAAAGCAAUAUGAAAGUGUCAGUGAUUUAUUUAAUACCAAAAAAAGUGUUUUGCAAGAUCACUUUUCUAAGUUAUUGAAUGAUCAAUGCAAGAACUUUAAUGACUGGUUCAGCAACAUUAAAGUGAACCUUAAGGAGUGUUUUGAAUCAUCAGAAACAAAAAAGAGUGUGGAACAAAAGCUACAAAAACUUUCUGAUUUCUUGACUCUUGAAGGAAGAAACAGUAAAAUAAAGCAGGUGGACAGCGUACUGAAGCAUGUGAAGAAGCAUCUGCCCAAAGCACAUGUGAAGGAGCUUAUCAGUUGGCUCGUGGGUCAGGAAUUCGAAUUAGAAAAAAUGGAGUCCAUAUGCCAGGCUCGAGCAAAGGAGCUUGAAGACUCCUUGCAGCAGCUACUGAGACUCCAGGAUGACCAUAGAAACCUGAGGAAGUGGUUGACUAAUCAAGAAGAGAAAUGGAAAGGAAUGGAAGAACCAGGGGAGAAAACUGAGCUGUUCUGCCAAGCUUUAGCUAGAAAGAGGGAACAGUUUGAAUCUGUGGCCCAAUUGAACAACUCUUUGAAGGAAUAUGGGUUUACUGAAGAAGAAGAAAUAAUAAUGGAAGCAACAUGUUUGAUGGAUAGAUACCAGACAUUACUGAGACAACUAAGUGAAAUCGAGGAAGAGGAUAAGUUACUACCCACAGAGGACCAGAGCUUUAAUGAUCUUGCACAUGAUGUAAUUCAUUGGAUAAAAGAGAUUAAAGAGUCCCUUAUGGUUUUGAAUUCAUCCGAAGGCAAAAUGCCACUUGAGGAAAGAAUCCAAAAAAUCAAGGAAAUCAUUUUGCUGAAGCCUGAAGGGGAUGCCAGAAUAGAGACCAUCAUGAAGCAGGCUGAGAGCAGCGAGGCCCCGCUGGUUCAGAAGACCCUCACUGACAUCAGCAACCAGUGGGACAACACACUCCAUUUAGCUAGCACCUACCUAAGCCAUCAAGAAAAGCUUCUACUAGAAGGAGAGAAAUAUUUACAAAGUAAGGAGGAUCUGAGAUUAAUGCUCAUAGAACUAAAGAAGAAACAGGAAGCAGGCUUUGCUCUACAACAUGGUCUGCAGGAGAAGAAAGCUCAGUUAAAGAUUUAUAAGAAAUUCCUCAAGAAAGCCCAAGAUUUGACAUCCUUGCUAAAGGAGUUAAAAUCUCAGGGAAACUACCUCUUGGAGUGCACUAAAAAUCCCAGCUUCAGUGAAGAGCCUUGGCUGGAAAUAAAGCAUCUACACGAAAGUCUUCUUCAACAACUGCAGGAUUCUGUGCAAAACUUGGACGGUCACGUUCGAGAACAUGAUUCAUACCAGGUUUGCGUCACAGACCUGAAUACUACAUUGGACAAUUUCUCCAAGGAAUUUGUCAGUUUUUCUGAUAAGCCUGUGGAUCAAAUAGCGGUUGAGGAAAAAUUGCAGAAACUGCAGGAACUAGAGAAUAGACUCAGUUUACAAGAUGGCACAUUAAAGAAGAUUUUAGCUUUAGCAAAAUCCGUCAAGCAAAAUACAUCUUCAGUGGGGCAGAAGAUUAUUAAAGAUGAUAUAAAAUCACUUCAGUGUAAACAAAAAGAUUUGGAAAACAGGCUUGCAUCUGCUAAGCAGGAGAUGGAAUGUUGUCUCAACAGCAUUCUCAAAUCAAAACGCUCAACAGAAAAGAAAGGAAAGUUUACUCUGCCAGGCAGAGAGAAGCAGGCCACUUCUGAUGUGCAGGAGUCUACUCAGGAAUCAGCUGCAGUGGAAAAGUUGGAGGAAGACUGGGAAAUAAACAAGGAUUCAGCUGUGGAAAUGGCUAUGUCAAAACAACUUUCUCUUAAUGCUCAAGAAAGCAUGAAAAACACUGAAGAUGAGCGGAAAGUCAAUGAGCUGCAAAAUCAACCUUUAGAAUUAGAUACUAUGUUAAGAAAUGAACAAUUAGAAGAGAUAGAGAAAUUAUAUACCCAGUUGGAAGCAAAGAAAGCAGCCAUUAAGCCACUGGAACAAACAGAAUGUCUUAACAAAACAGAAACUGGGGCCUUGGUUCUCCACAAUAUAGGAUAUUCGGCACAGCAUUUGGACAAUUUGCUUCAGGCACUUAUUACUUUGAAGAAAAACAAAGAAAGCCAAUAUUGUGUCCUCAGAGAUUUUCAGGAAUACCUUGCUGCAGUUGAAUCUUCAAUGAAAGCCUUGUUGACAGACAAGGAAAGUCUUAAAGUAGGACCACUGGACAGUGUAACGUAUCUGGACAAAAUUAAAAAAUUCAUAGCAUCCAUAGAAAAAGAGAAAGAUUCUUUAGGCAACUUGAAAAUCAAAUGGGAGAAUUUAUCAAACCACGUGACUGACAUGGAUAAGAAAUUGUUGGAAAGCCAGAUUAAGCAACUUGAACAUGGUUGGGAACAAGUGGAACAGCAGAUUCAAAAGAAGUAUUCUCAGCAGGUAGUGGAAUAUGAUGAAUUUACAACCCUCAUGAAUAAGGUACAGGACACUGAGAUUUCUCUGCAACAGCAGCAGCAACAUCUACAGUUAAGGCUGAAGUCUCCAGAAGAACGGGCAGGGAACCAAAGCAUGAUUGCCUUGACCACUGACCUCCAGGCUACCAAGCAUGGAUUUUCUGUUUUAAAGGGGCAAGCUGAACUUCAGAUGAAGAGGAUUUGGGGAGAAAAAGAAAAGAAGAAUUUGGAGGAUGGAAUAAAUAACUUGAAGAAACAAUGGGAAACAUUGGAGCCAUUACACUUAGAAGCAGAAAAUCAGAUUAAGAAGUGUGACAUAAGGAACAAGAUGAAAGAGACUAUCUUAUGGGCCAAGAAUUUGUUGGGUGAACUUAAUCCCUCCAUUCCCCUUCUCCCAGAUGACAUUCUUUCACAGAUCAGAAAGUGCAAAGUGACACAUGAUGGCAUUCUAGCUAGGCAGCAGUCUGUGGAAUCGUUGGCUGAAGAGGUCAAAGAUAAGGUUCCUAGCCUUACAACCUAUGAGGGCAGUGAUUUAAAUAAUACCCUAGAGGACUUACGGAAUCAAUACCAAAUGCUGGUUUUAAAAUCAACUCAAAGAUCACAGCAAUUAGAAUUUAAGUUGGAAGAAAGAAGCAAUUUUUUUGCUAUAAUAAGGAAGUUUCAACUUAUGGUUCAAGAAAGUGAAACACUGAUAAUUCCCAGGGUGGAGACAGCUGCCACGGAAGCUGAACUAAAACAUCACCAUGUUACUUUGGAGGCAUCUCAGAAGGAAUUGCAAGAAAUUGACAGUGGAAUCUCAACACAUCUUCAGGAGCUAACAAACAUCUAUGAGGAGCUGAAUGUGUUUGAAAGAUUAUUUCUGGAAGAUCAGUUGAAAAAUCUUAAGAUUAGGACCAACAGAAUACAAAGAUUCAUUCAGAAUACAUGUAAUGAAGUGGAACACAAGAUAAAGUUUUGCAGACAAUUCCAUGAAAAAACAUCAGCGCUUCAGGAGGAGGCUGACAGUAUACAGCGCAAUGAACUAUUACUUAAUCAAGAAGUAAAUAAAGGUGUUAAAGAGGAGAUCUAUAAUCUUAAAGACAGACUCACCGCUAUUAAGUGUUGCAUCUUACAGGUAUUGAAACUUAAAAAAGUGUUUGACUAUAUUGGACUAAACUGGGAUUUUUCACAACUUGACCAAUUACAAACCCAAGUAUUUGAAAAAGAAAAGGAACUUGAAGAAAAAAUUAAGCAGUUGGACACAUUUGAGGAAGAACAUGGCAAAUAUCAGGCAUUAUUAAGUAAAAUGAGAGCUAUUGAUUUGCAAAUUAAGAAAAUGACUGAAGUAGUACUAAAAGCUCCUGAUAGCUCUCCGGAAAGCAGACGGCUCAAUGCCCAAAUUUUAAGUCAGAGAAUUGAGAAAGCCAAGUGUUUAUGUGAUGAGAUAAUAAAGAAAUUAAAUGAAAAUAAGACCUUUGAUGACUCAUUCAAGGAGAAAGAAAUACUACAAAUAAAGCUGAAUGCAGAAGAAAAUGAUAAGUUAUACAAAGUUCUCCAAAACAUGGUAUUAGAACUCUCACCAAAAGAAUUGGAUGAAAAGAAUUGUCAGGACAAACUAGAAACUUCCUUACAUGUUUUAAAUCAGAUAAAAUCUCAAUUACAGCAGCCAUUACUUAUAAAUUUGGAAAUUAAACAUAUUCAAAAUGAAAAGGACAAUUGUGAAGCAUUUCAGGAGCAAGUUUGGGCAGAAAUGUGUAGUAUUAAAGCUGUGACUGCUAUUGAGAAACAAAGAGAAGAAAACUCUUCUGAAGCGAGUGAUGUGGAGACAAAACUACGUGAGUUUGAAGAUCUUCAGAUGCAGCUUAACACAAGCAUUGAUUUGCGCACAAAUGUCUUGAAUGAUGCUUAUGAAAAUCUAACACGCUAUAAAGAAGCAGUCACCAGGGCAGUGGAGAGCAUCACUUCCCUCGAAGCCAUCAUUAUACCCUACAGAGUAGAUGUUGGUAAUCCAGAAGAAUCUUUAGAGAUGCCUCUUCGAAAACAAGAGGAAUUGGAAUCCACAGUAGCACACAUCCAGGACCUCACUGAGAAACUGGGAAUGAUAUCCAGCCCCGAAGCCAAACUACAACUUCAGUAUACUUUACAGGAACUAGUUUCUAAGAACUCAGCAAUGAAGGAAGCUUUCAAAGCACAGGAAACUGAGGCAGAAAGGUAUCUUGAGAAUUACAAAUGCUAUAGAAAAAUGGAAGAGGAUAUUUACACUAACCUCAGCAAAAUGGAGACAGUUCUUGGACAGUCCAUGUCCUCGUUGCCACUGUCUUACAGAGAAGCUUUAGAGCGCUUGGAACAGAGCAAGGCCUUGGUGUCAAAUCUUAUAUCAACCAAAGAAGAGUUAAUGAAACUACGACAGAUCCUUAGACUCUUGAGACUCAGGUGCACAGAAAAUGAUGGCAUAUGUUUGCUCAAGAUUGUGUCGGCUCUGUGGGAGAAAUGGCUGAGUUUGCUGGAAGCUGCUAAAGAGUGGGAGAUGUGGUGCGAAGAACUGAAGCAGGAAUGGAAAUUUGUCAGUGAAGAAAUUGAACGAGAGGCAAUUAUUUUAGAUAAUCUUCAGGAAGAACUCCCUGAAAUUUCCAAAACAAAAGAGGCAGCCACCACAGAGGAACUCUCUGAGCUGCUAGACUGUUUAUGCCAAUAUGGAGAGAACGUGGAGAAGCAACAGCUGUUACUGACUCUACUUCUUCAGCGCAUCAGAAGUAUCCAGAAUGUUCCUGAAAGCUCAGGGGCUGUGGAAACUGUUCCAGCAUUUCAAGAAAUUACUUCUAUGAAAGAACGAUGCAACAAGCUUCUUCAGAAAGUUCAGAAAAAUAAAGAAUUGGUGCAGACUGAAAUCCAAGAAAGACAUUCCUUCACAAAAGAGAUAAUUGCUUUGAAGAAUUUCUUUCAACAGACCACAACUUCAUUCCAAAAUAUGGCAUUCCAGGAUCACCCAGAAAAGUCAGAACAAUUUGAGGAGCUUCAAAGCAUCCUUAAGAAAGGGAAACUAACUUUUGAGAAUAUUAUGGAAAAACUGCGAAUCAAGUAUUCCGAAAUGUACACCAUAGUCCCUGCAGAGAUUGAAUCCCAGGUGGAAGAAUGCAGAAAAGCUUUAGAAGACAUAGAUGAGAAGAUUAGCAAUGAAGUCUUAAAAAGCUCACCAUCAUAUGCAAUGAGGAGAAAAAUAGAAGAAAUUAACAAUGGGCUUCAUAAUGUUGAAAAGAUGUUGCAGCAGAAAAGCAAAAAUAUUGAGAAAGCUCAAGAAAUUCAAAAGAAAAUGUGGGACGAGUUAGAUCUAUGGCAUUCCAAACUAAAUGAGCUGGAUUCUGAAGUUCAGGACAUUGUUGAACAGGACCCAGGACAGGCUCAAGAAUGGAUGGAUAACUUGAUGAUUCCUUUCCAGCAGUAUCAGCAAGUAUCACAGAGAGCAGAGUGUAGAACCUCACAGUUGAAUAAGGCCACAGUUAAGAUGGAGGAAUAUAGUGACCUUCUGAAGAGCACUGAGGCUUGGAUAGAAAAUACCAGUCAUUUGCUGGCCAAUCCUGCUGACUAUGACUCUUUGAGGACACUGAGUCACCAUGCUAGCACUGUGCAGAUGGCUUUGGAAGAUUCAGAACAGAAGCACAAUCUUUUACAUUCAAUCUUUAUGGAUCUAGAAGACCUGUCAAUAAUUUUUGAAACAGAUGAAUUAACCCAAUCCAUACAAGAGUUAAGUAAUCAAGUAACAGCUUUACAACAAAAAAUAAUGGAAAGCCUUCCACAGAUUCAGCGAAUGGCUGAUGAUGUGGUUGCUAUUGAAUCUGAAGUAAAAUCAAUGGAAAAAAGAGUUUCAAAAAUCAAAACUAUCCUAUUAUCAAAAGAAAUAUUUGAUUUUUCACCUGAAGAACAUCUCAAACAUGGGGAGGUCAUACUUGAAAAUAUACGUCCCAUGAAGAAAACCAUUGCUGAGAUAGUGUCUUACCAAGUGGAACUGAGGUUGCCCCAAACAGGAAUGAAACCUCUGCCUGUGUUUCAGCGGACAAAUCAGCUUUUACAAGAUAUAAAACUAUUGGAAAAUGUGACUCAAGAACAAAAUGAGUUAUUAAAGGUAGUCAUAAAACAGACCAAUGAAUGGGAUGAAGAAAUAGAAAAUUUGAAACAGAUCUUAAAUAAUUAUUCAGCUCAGUUCUCCCUUGAACAUAUGUCACCAGACCAAGCUGACAAGCUGCCACAACUACAGGGAGAAAUCGAACGUAUGGAGAAACAGAUUCUGAGUUUGAACCAGAGAAAAGAAGACCUGUUGGUGGACUUGAAGGCCACCGUACUAAACCUUCACCAGCAUUUGAAGCAAGAACAAGAAGGAGUAGAAAGAGAUAGGCUGCCAGCUGUAACAUCAGAGGAAGGUGGAGUGGCAGAGAGGGAUGCUUCUGAGCGGAAGUUGAACAGAAGAGGCUCCAUGUCUUACCUGGCAGCAGUCGAGGAAGAGGUGGAAGAAAGUUCCGUGAAGAGCGAUAAUGGAGAUGAGAAGGCAGAGCCAUCGCCUCAGUCUUGGUCUUCACUUUGGAAGCAUGACAAGGACAUGGAAGAAGACAGAGCUUCCUCAUCCUCUGGAACAAUUGUUCAGGAAGCAUAUGGGAAAAUAAGCACCUCUGAUAAUUCCAUGGCACAAAUCCUCACACCAGACUCACUAAACACUGAGCAAGGCCCAGAAUGUUCCCUAAGGCCCAACCAAACAGAAGAGGGCACCACACCUCCUAUUGAGGCUGACACUCUGGACUCUUCUGACGCGCAAGGAGGUUUGGAGCCCAGGGUGGAGAAAACUAGGCCGGAGCCCACAGAAGUCCUGCAUGCCUGCAAGACCCAGGUGGCCGAGCUGGAGCUGUGGCUGCAACAAGCCAACGUGGCAGUUGAGCCGGAAACAUUAAACGCAGACAUGCAGCAGGUGCUGGAACAGCAGCUGGUAGGGUGCCAGGCUAUGCUAACAGAGAUUGAGCACAAGGUUGCCUUUCUGUUAGAGACUUGCAAAGAUCAGGGCCUGGGAGAUAAUGGAGCCACUCAACAUGAGGCUGAAGCGCUUUCCCUGAAACUGAAAACAGUGAAGUGCAAUUUAGAAAAAGUCCAGAUGAUGCUUCAGGAGAAGCACAGUGAAGAUCAGCAUCCUACCAUUCUAAAGAAAUCCUCAGAGCCAGAGCAUCAAGAAGCUCUCCAACCAGUUAACCUUUCUGAAUUGGAAUCCAUUGUAACUGAAAGGCCACAAUUCAGCAGACAAAAAGAUUUCCAGCAGCAACAGGUUCUGGAGUUAAAACCAAUGGAACAGAAAGAUUUCAUCAAAUUCAUAGAAUUUAAUGCUAAGAAAAUGUGGCCCCAGUAUUGCCAACAUGAUAACGAUACAACUCAGGAAUCAUCUGCAAGCAACCAGGCAUCCAGCCCUGAAAAUGACGUUCCAGACUCGAUCUUGUCACCCCAGGGCCAAAAUGGAGAUAAGUGGCAAUAUCUGCAUCAUGAACUCUCAUCAAAAAUAAAGCUCCCACUCCCUCAGCUUGUGGAGCCUCAGGUUUCCACAAAUAUGGGUAUUCUACCCAGCGUGACUAUGUAUAACUUUAGAUACCCAACAACUGAAGAACUGAAAACCUAUACCACCCAACUUGAAGACCUGCGCCAAGAAGCAAGUAACCUUCAGACACAGGAAAAUAUGACAGAAGAAGCAUAUAUCAAUUUGGAUAAAAAAUUGUUUGAACUAUUCCUGACCCUCAGUCAGUGCCUCAGCAGUGUGGAGGAGAUGCUGGAGAUGCCCAGACUUUACAGGGAGGAUGGUUCUGGCCAGCAGGUGCACUACGAGACGCUGGCUCUUGAGUUGAAGAAACUUUAUUUAGCGCUAAGUGACAAGAAGGGUGAUCUUUUGAAAGCCAUGACUUGGCCUGGCGAGAACACCAACUUGCUCCUUGAAUGUUUUGACAACCUUCAAGUCUGCCUGGAGCACACUCAGGCUGCAGCUGUCUGUAGAAGCAAGUCCCUGAAAGCUGGCCUCGAUUACAACCGCAGUUACCAGAAUGAAAUAAAGAGAUUAUAUCAUCAGCUCAUUAAGAGUAAGACAUCUUUACAACAGUCUUUGAAUGAAAUCAGUGGGCAGAGUGUUGCUGAACAGCUUCAGAAAGCAGAUGCAUAUACAGUGGAGCUGGAGAACGCCGAGAGCCGAGUGGCCAAACUAAGAGAUGAAGGGGAGAGGCUUCAUUUACCUUAUGCUUUACUCCAGGAGGUUUACAAAUUAGAGGAUGUACUUGACAGUAUGUGGGGAAUGCUAAGAGCCAGGUACACAGAACUCAGCAGCCCUUUCGUCACUGAGAGCCAGCAAGAUGCUUUGUUGCAAGGCAUGGUGGAACUGGUGAAGAUUGGGAAGGAAAAGCUUGCUCAUGGCCACUUAAAACAAACCAAAAGUAAAGUGGCGUUACAGGCUCAAAUAGAAAAUCACAAGGUUUUUUUCCAGAAGCUUGUUGCUGACAUGUUGUUGAUCCAAGCAUACUCUGCCAAAAUACUUCCUUCUUUAUUGCAAAACAGAGAGACAUUUUGGGCAGAACAAGUAACAGAAGUUAAAAUACUAGAAGAAAAGUCACGCCAAUGUGGUAUGAAGCUGCAGAGUUUGUUGCAGAAAUGGGAAGAAUUUGAUGAAAACUAUGCAUCUCUUGAAAAGGACCUGGAAAUUCUUAUAUCUACAUUGCCCUCUGUGAGUUUGGUGGAAGAAACAGAGGAAAGAUUAGUGGAAAGGAUUUCAUUUUACCAGCAAAUAAAAAGAAACAUUGGUGGAAAACACGCCCGGCUUUACCAAACUCUGAACGAAGGCAAACAGUUGGUGGCGUCUGUGAGCUGUCCUGAAUUAGAGGGCCAGAUCGCAAAACUGGAAGAGCAGUGGUUGUCCCUGAACAAGAAAAUUGACCAUGAGCUCCACAGGCUGCAAGCUCUUCUCAAGCAUCUGCUCAGUUAUAACAGAGAUUCGGAUCAGUUAACCAAGUGGUUGGAAUCUUCCCAGCAUACUCUGAAUUACUGGAAAGAACAGUCCCUCAAUGUGUCUCAGGACUUGGAUACAAUCAGAAGCAACAUCAACAAUUUUUUUGAGUUUUCAAAAGAAGUUGAUGAAAAAUCCUCCUUGAAGACUGCCGUUAUCAGUAUCGGGAACCAGCUUCUUCACCUGAAAGAAACUGAUACAGCUACACUGAGAGCUUCUUUAGCACAGUUUGAACAAAAAUGGACAAUGCUCAUAACUCAACUUCCAGAUAUUCAAGAAAAACUUCACCAGCUUCAAAUGGAGAAAUUGCCGUCUCGUAAAGCAAUCACAGAAAUGAUUAGCUGGAUGAACAAUGUGGAGCAUCAAACUUCAGAUGAAGACUCCGUGCAUUCACCAAGUUCUGCAUCUCAAGUUAAACAUCUUCUUCAGAAGCACAAGGAGUUUAGAAUGGAAAUGGACUAUAAACAGUGGAUAGUUGACUUCGUUAACCAGUCAUUACUUCAGCUAAGCACCUGUGAUGUAGAAAGCAAGCGCUAUGAAAGAACGGAGUUUGCAGAGCACCUGGGGGAGAUGAACCGCCAGUGGCACCGUGUACAUGGAAUGCUGAAUAGAAAGAUACAACAUUUAGAACAACUUCUAGAAAGUAUCACUGAGAGUGAAAAUAAAAUACAGAUCUUGAACAACUGGCUGGAAGCACAAGAAGAGAGACUGAAAACUUUACAAAAACCUGAAAGUGUGAUCUCAGUGCAGAAGCUGCUCCUGGACUGUCAGGAUAUAGAAAAUCAACUUGCAAUUAAAUCCAAAGCACUAGAUGAGUUGAAACAAAGUUAUCUGACUUUGGAGAGUGGGGCAGUGCCAUUGUUAGAAGAUACAGCAUCCCGAAUUGAUGAGUUAUUUCAAAAGAGAAGCAGUGUUCUCACUCAGGUCAAUCAGCUCAAAACCUCCAUGCAGUCAGUUUUACAGGAGUGGAAGAUUUAUGAUCAACUCUAUGAUGAAGUGAAUAUGAUGACAAUCCGAUUCUGGUACUGCAUGGAACACAGCAAGCCUGUGGUGUUAUCAUUGGAGACCUUGAGAUGCCAGGUGGAGAACCUUCAGUCUCUGCAAGAUGAAGCUGAGAGCAGUGAAGGGAGUUGGGAGAAACUCCAGGAGGUUAUCGGCAAACUCAAAGGUCUCUGCCCCUCUGUUGCUGAAAUAAUCGAAGAGAAAUGCCAAAAUACUCAUAAAAGGUGGACUCAGGUGAACCAAGCCAUUGCAGACCAGUUGCAGAAGGCCCAGAGUCUGCUCCAGCUCUGGAAGGCCUAUAGCAAUGCUCAUGGUGAAGCUGCCGCAAGGCUGAAGCAGCAGGAAGCAAAGUUUCAACAGCUCGCAAACAUCAGCAUGUCUGGAAACAACCUGGCAGAGAUCCUGCCCCCAGCCCUGCAGGACAUAAAGGAGCUGCAGCAUGAUGUGCAGAAAACAAAAGAAGCCUUUCUCCAAAAUUCCAGUGUCCUGGAUCGACUCCCACAACCCGCAGAGUCCAGCACCCACAUGCUCCUCCCGGGCCCCCUGCACUCUCUCCAGAGGGCUGCUUAUUUGGAAAAGAUGCUGCUUGUGAAAGCAAAUGAAUUUGAGUUUGUUCUCUCACAGUUUAAGGAUUUUGGAGUCCGGCUGGAAUCUUUAAAAGGUCUUAUUAUGCAUGAAGAAGAGAAUUUGGAUAGACUUCACCAACAGGAAAAAGAAAAUCCUGACUCAUUCCUGAAUCAUGUGCUGGCACUGACAGCCCAAUCACCUGAUAUUGAACAUUUGAAUGAAGUGAGCCUCAAGCUCCCACUUAGUGACGUAGCUGUGAAGACGUUACAAAAUAUGAACCGGCAAUGGAUUCGGGCCACGGCCACGGCACUGGAGCGCUGCAGUGAGCUUCAGGGAAUUGGAUUGAAUGAAAAGUUUCUUUAUUGCUGUGAAAAGUGGAUCCAACUUUUGGAGAAGAUAGAAGAAGCACUCAAAGUGGAUGUGGCUAACAGCCUUCCUGAGCUCCUGGAGCAGCAGAAAACCUAUAAGAUGUUAGAAGCUGAAGUUUCUAUAAACCAGACAAUUGCUGAUUCCUAUGUCACCCAGUCCUUACAACUCCUGGACACAACAGAAAUAGAGAACAGACCAGAAUUUAUUACAGAAUUCUCAAAGCUGACGGAUCGGUGGCAGAAUGCUGUCCAGGGUGUUCGGCAGAGGAAGGGUGACGUUGAUGGGCUGGUGAGGCAGUGGCAAGAUUUCACUACUUCUGUGGAGAACUUGUUUCGCUUCCUCACUGACACCAGCCACCUGCUAUCUGCAGUGAAGGGCCAGGAGCGCUUCAGCCUCUACCAAACCAGAAGUCUGAUCCAUGAGCUGAAGAAUAAAGAAAUUCAUUUUCAAAGGAGGCGAACUACCUGUGCCCUAACCUUGGAAGCUGGAGAAAAGUUACUGCUCACAACUGACCUGAAAACUAAAGAGUCUGUGGGUAGGAGAAUCAGUCAACUUCAGGACAGCUGGAAAGACAUGGAGCCCCAGCUGGCAGAGAUGAUUAAGCAGUUCCAGAGCACUGUAGAGACCUGGGACCAGUGUGAAAAGAAAAUCAAGGAGUUGAAAAGCAGGCUGCAAGUUUUAAAGGCACAAAGUGAAGAUCCUCUUCCAGAGCUUCACGAGGACCUCCAUAACGAAAAAGAGCUGAUUAAGGAACUAGAACAGUCUUUGGCUAGCUGGACUCAGAACUUGAAAGAACUUCAAACUAUGAAGGCGGACUUAACCCGGCACGUUCUCGUGGAAGAUGUGAUGGUUUUGAAGGAGCAAAUAGAGCAUUUGCACAGACAAUGGGAGGACCUCUGCUUAAGGGUGGCCAUACGUAAACAGGAGAUUGAAGACAGACUCAAUACAUGGGUUGUAUUCAAUGAAAAAAAUAAAGAGUUGUGUGCCUGGCUGGUGCAGAUGGAAAACAAAGUUCUACAGACAGCGGACAUUAGUAUUGAAGAAAUGAUUGAAAAGUUACAGAAGGACUGCAUGGAAGAAAUAAACUUGUUUAGUGAAAACAAGUUACAGUUAAAGCAGAUGGGUGACCAGUUGAUCAAGGCCAGCAACAAAUCAAGAGCAGCUGAGAUCGAUGACAAGCUCAACAAAAUUAACGAUCGUUGGCAACAUCUUUUUGAUGUCAUCGGAUCAAGGGUGAAGAAGCUGAAGGAGACCUUUGCUUUUAUUCAGCAGUUGGACAAAAACAUGAGCAACCUUCGCACCUGGUUGGCUCGAAUUGAGUCUGAGCUUUCCAAGCCUGUUGUUUAUGAUGUCUGCGAUGAUCAAGAGAUCCAGAAGAGGCUCGCUGAGCAGCAGGAUCUACAGCGAGAUAUUGAACAACACAGCGCAGGGGUGGAGUCCGUGUUUAACAUCUGUGACGUCCUACUGCACGACUCCGAUGCCUGUGCAAAUGAGACCGAGUGUGACUCGAUCCAGCAGACCACCAGGAGCCUGGACAGACGCUGGAGGAACAUUUGUGCCAUGUCCAUGGAGCGGCGCAUGAAAAUCGAGGAGACGUGGCGCCUGUGGCAGAAGUUUUUAGACGACUAUUCUCGCUUUGAGGACUGGCUCAAGUCAGCUGAGAGGACGGCAGCCUGCCCAAAUUCCUCAGAGGUGUUGUACACGAGUGCCAAAGAGGAACUGAAGAGGUUUGAGGCCUUUCAGCGGCAGAUUCAUGAGCGGCUCACUCAGCUGGAGCUCAUCAACAAGCAGUACCGGCGGCUGGCCCGGGAGAACCGCACAGACACGGCCAGCAGGCUGAAGCAGAUGGUCCACGAGGGCAACCAGCGCUGGGACAACCUUCAGAGGCGGGUCACAGCCGUCCUGCGGAGACUCAGGCAUUUCACCAACCAGAGGGAAGAAUUUGAGGGCACCAGGGAGAGCAUUCUGGUGUGGCUCACAGAGAUGGACCUGCAGCUGACCAACGUGGAGCACUUCUCAGAGAGUGACGCCGAUGACAAGAUGCGCCAACUGAAUGGCUUCCAACAGGAAAUUACAUUAAAUACCAACAAGAUUGAUCAGCUCAUUGUGUUUGGGGAGCAGCUGAUUCAGAAGAGCGAGCCCCUGGAUGCUGUGCUGAUUGAGGAUGAGCUGGAGGAACUCCACCGCUACUGCCAGGAGGUGUUUGGAAGGGUCUCCCGGUUCCACCGGCGGCUCACCUCCUGCACUCCGGGCUUGGAAGAUGAAAAGGAGGCCUCUGAGAAUGAAACAGACAUGGAAGACCCCAGAGAAAUCCAGACUGAUUCUUGGCGUAAACGGGGAGAGAGCGAGGAACCGUCAUCUCCUCAGUCCCUGUGUCAUCUAGUGGCCCCAGGGCACGAGCGGUCUGGCUGCGAGACCCCUGUCAGCGUGGACUCCAUCCCCCUGGAGUGGGACCACACAGGCGACGUGGGGGGCUCCUCCUCUCACGAAGAGGACGAGGAGGGCCCAUACUACAGCGCACUGUCAGAUGUAGAAAUCCCUGAAAAUCCUGAGGCAUAUCUUAAAAUGACCACAAAAACUUUGAAAGCGUCUUCUGGUAAAUCCAUUUCGGAUGGCCACUCGUGGCAUGUUCCCGACAGCCCUUCCUGUCCCGAGCAUCACUACAAGCAAAUGGAAGGUGACAGGAAUGUUCCACCUGUUCCCCCUGCGUCCAGCACCCCUUAUAAACCACCCUAUGGAAAGCUACUAUUACCUCCAGGCACGGAUGGUGGCAAAGAAGGCCCGCGAGUCCUGAAUGGCAACCCACAGCAGGAAGACGGGGGACUGGCCGGUAUCACAGAGCAGCAGUCAGGUACUGCCUGUAACUGGCAGUCGUCCAGAGAGGCAGAGUAUGGUGCCUUCGACAGAUGGGAGAUGAUUCAAGCACAGGAGCUUCACAAUAAGCUCAAAAUAAAACAAAAUUUGCAACAGCUGAACUCUGAUAUCAGCGCCAUCACUACUUGGCUGAAAAAAACUGAAGCAGAGCUGGAAAUGUUAAAGAUGGCAAAGCCUCCCUCUGAUAUCCAGGAAAUAGAACUGAGAGUGAAGAGACUGCAGGAGAUACUGAAAGCCUUUGACACUUACAAGGCAUUAGUGGUCUCUGUCAACGUGAGCAGCAAGGAAUUUCUGCAAACCGAGAGCCCCGAAUCCACAGAGCUCCAAAGUAGACUCCGCCAGCUGAGCCUGCUCUGGGAAGCAGCACAGGGCGCAGUGGACAGCUGGAGAGGGGGCUUACGACAGUCGCUCAUGCAGUGCCAGGGCUCUAAGACACGGCCGCGCUCUGAUGUGUUGUUUUUUAAGGACUUCCACCAGUUGAGUCAAAAUCUGCUGCUGUGGUUAGCGAGUGCCAAGAACCGGAGGCAGAAGGCUCAUGUCACCGAUCCAAAGGCAGACCCCCGGGCUCUCCUAGAGUGUCGGAGGGAACUAAUGCAACUGGAAAAGGAGCUGGUAGAACGUCAACCUCAAGUGGACAUGUUACAGGAGAUUUCAAACAGCCUUCUCAUUAAGGGACAUGGAGAAGACUGUAUUGAAGCUGAAGAAAAGGUGCAUGUUAUUGAGAAGAAACUCAAACAGUUACGGGAGCAAGUGUCCCAAGAUUUAAUGGCCUUGCAGGGAACCCAGAACCCAGCCUCACCCCUGCCCAGCUUCGACGAGGUAGACUCGGGGGACCAGCCUCCUGCAACAUCCGUGCCAGCUCCCCGAGCAAAGCAGUUCAGAGCAGUGAGAACUACAGAAGGCGAGGAGGAGACAGAGAGCAGGGUCCCCGGCAGCACACGGCCACAGCGCUCCUUCCUCUCAAGGGUGGUCCGGGCAGCCCUACCCCUGCAGCUGCUCCUCCUGCUGCUGCUGCUCCUGGCCUGCCUGCUGCCCUCCUCCGAAGAAGACUACAGCUGCACUCAGGCCAACAACUUUGCCCGGUCCUUUUACCCCAUGCUGAGGUACACCAAUGGGCCACCCCCCACAUAGAGGGCAUAGCUGGCCACAGUGCUACACCACCUGCCUGAUUGCCAAGGGUGCCCAGCACGUGGCCCCAGACCAAUCUGAGUGACUUAGUGUUGGCAAGGUCCCGGGACCUGUGCAGACUUCUUCUGGGCUUACCCAGCACGGGCUCCCUGGAGCCCAGGGCAGCUUUCAGAUUGUGUUCCUCCCCAGGAGCAGGGAACCUGUGUGGCAGGUGCCCCGGGUAUUUUGGCAGAACUAGUUGAUUAGUUUAGGGAUCUCUGGAAAUGUCAGUUUCCUGAAGAGCCAAGCACUUUGUGAAUUCUGGUUUGUUUGUAAAACAGCAUUAUUAUAAUGUAGGUAUGGUCAAUGAGCAGUGGUGUCCAUCACAUAUAUUAUAGAAGCAAGCGAGGACAUUCCACCCUAGAAAUGGUUCAGAAACUCAUAGGCACCCUUAGCUGAUGGAAACAAUCAAUCAUAUUUAAUACGCUUAGAAUCAGUUUUACUCCAAUCAGCUGGCAAUUUUGAGCUGCCGGUUAUACACCAAAAUGUUCUGUUCAGUACCUAGCUCUGCUCUUUUAUAUUGCUUUAAAUUUUUAAAGAAAUUGUAUUGCAUGGAUGUGGUUAUUUGUGCAUAUUUUUUAACAAUGCCCAAUCUGUAUGAAUAAUGUAAACUUCGAUUUUUUUUUAAAAAAAUUAGAUUUUAGCUGGAGCUUUUGACUAAUGUAAAGUAAAUGCCAAACUACCGACUUGAUAGGGAUGUUUUUGUAAGUUAAUUUUCUAAGACUUUUUCACAUCCAAAGUGAUGCUUUGCUUUGGGUUUUAACUGUUUGGCCACGGCGGGGGUGGGGGCGGGGGGUUGGUACAGAAACUUGAAGCUGUUUGUGAUAUGUACAACUCAGAUGUUUCUCAUUAAAAAACAAAAUUAGCCAGACUUCUGUUGUACUGAA